UGGUUUUCGUGGCUCUGAAUCUGCCCUCUGCCAGGUGCACUCUUCUGUCAUCCUCCAUGGCUACCUCUGAGGAAGGUGCUGGAAGACAUGCUCUCCUUCAUGGCUGAGCAGAUUUCUUAACCUGCUUCCUGCCCAUAGGAAGGAUGAAUGCCGAGGAUCGUUUUAGAUCUCAAAUGCCACGGUCUAUGUUAAUCCAGCCGAAAGUGUAGUUAUCGAUUUGUCCCUUUUGAAGCUGUCCUGUUUGUUUUUAAUCUCUUUGAUUCCGGUCAACCCCGUGUGCCUACAGUCAUUUUUCGUGCAUGUCCUCCUUUCUCUAAACUCAAUUCCAAGUACACUGAGCACAUCAUGCUUCCAACAGGCCAAAUUCUGGGUCUCUUUCUCUAGGCCAUUUUGUGCAGUUGAAAGAUUUCAUUGGGGACCUUGAUAAUCCAACUAAAGGUUUCGGCGCAAGAGCCAAUGAUUGCAUCUUUGAUUUGGUCUUUACCCGUAGGCUGUGCUUUCACGGCCAACCUUAAUUUGGUGAGAAAUUGCUUCACUUUAAAAUCCUGAAAAUGUUGUAUUUUCUCUCUUCCCUUUCAAUUGUAUUUGCAAAGCAGUGAGUUUUUUGGGAGGAGGCAAGGUGCAUUUUUUUUUCCUUAUAGCACGGUGUCAAAGGCAUUCUAUAACACCAGUUCACACAGGCAAGAUUCUGUUUUGAAAACAAGUUUAGUUAGGCCAAUUUUCUAAGUUAUCAUAGGUUAUUUCUUUUUUCUUUUUCUUUUUUUGCCGGGUGUUUUAACACUGCAUAUCUUGGGUUGCCAUUUUUCCAACUUCCUUUAACAACUUUCCAGCUUGCCAUCACCUAAACCCAAAACCAAUGACCCAUAUUUCAGGUUUUUGUAAUGGCAGCCCUACUUCUGUGUACCAAUUUCUGUAUUAGCUUUUGCUGCAGUAACUAGCAAUUCUCAAAUCUCCAUGGCUUCCAACAACAAACACUUAUUUUUCACUUAAGAAUCCUGCGAGUCAGCUGCAGCUCUGCCGAGCUUGGCUGUGUUCUCCACGUCUCCUCAUGCCAGGCUGAGGCUGAAUGAGCAGCUGCCAUCUGGGCCCUGCUCUUCUCAUGCUGGAGGGCAGGAGCUCCGGAGGGGAAGCGGGAACCCCCAGGAUCUCAUAAAGCCUCUGCUGGGACCUGGCAGCCGUCCCCUCCUCCCACAAGUCAUAUGGCAAGCCCAAGGUUAAUGGGGUGAGCCUGUACCCUUCACCUCCUGGCAAGUCACGAUGAGGAGAGGGCAGAGACAAAUCAUUUUGAACAAGUGAUACAGUCUCUCACAGGCAUAGAUUCCAAAAAGAAACCCAGGAGAGAGUCACCAUGCCUCAAAUCAAGAACAGCCAUAUUGCAUUUCUAUCAAGGCAGAAGCACAGGUGUGACAGUGUGACAAUGAACCCUGAGACCGGAGGCCCUCCAGUCCAGGUGGACAUCCAGCUAUGCAGCCAGCUCAGUGCAGCCGAAAGAACCUGGGAGGCAGUCCGGAAAGCUGAGUUCCUCUUACCCGUAUCCCUGCAGCAAGCCACUUUCCCUCUGUGGAUCUCAAGUUCCUCUUCAAUAUUAACCAAGAGUUAAGCAGAAUCGUGGGUUGCUUUCGAGGAUGCCGUUCUGAUCUCUGCCAGCGCACUUCACAUGGCAGGGAACAGGCUGCCUUCCCAGGAGGCCGAGCUGCAGUAGAAGGAGCAUGAGUUUAGGAAUCAGGCCAAUUUGAGCGGGAAGCCCAGGCAGCCGUUUACCAGGUGUGGGUCCAUCAUAUACCCUCUGACUCUGUUUCCUCAUCUGUGAAGUGAACAUCACAGCAUCUAACUCUCAGGGCUGUGGGUAGGAUAAUUAUUUUAUACAGUGCCUUUUGCUAGGAAAUUUUUUGUUGUGUUGAGUCAAAAUCUGAUCCCUUAACCAGUGAACUCCGGCCCCGGUUCUGCCUCUGCCUGGGGCAGCAAAACAGUGAUUAGGAAUAUGGGCACGGGGGUCAUCCCACCUGGGUCUGAAUCGCACUGUCUGCUCCUGGUCAGGAUGGCCGGGGGGAGGAUCCUUAAUGCCCCCGCGGUUGGCUUGCUAUGCUUAUCUGUAAAUGAGCUACUGAUAAUAUCAACUUCAUAGUUUUGUUGUGGGGAUAAAUGAGCCGGUGCAUGCAAACUCAAGUAGCUGUUAUUAUUUCAGUUGGCAGCUCCUCAGGUACCUGAGCCUGCUUUCCAUACCUUCUGGGUCAUCCCGUAUUUCUUCAGGGUAAGCAACCUCACAUUUCUCCAGCAUUCUGUAGAUGUCAAGCUUUCUGCAAUCCUCCCCCGUCUAGCUGUCCUCUUGAGAAUCUCCUUCAGGAGCUCUGGUUAAGAGAUAAAGAAACAGUGAGGGCAUUCGAGUUCAUUAUCCCAGCCACGAUGGCAUUCUAGAUGUCUCCACAGACAUUCAGGAUCUGCCCAGGGUCCCACAUCUGUCUCUUCUCCACAUCUUACCCUGCCUUCUCCAGGUGAUGGUGAUUUCGUGAUCCCAGUCACCUGCCCCCACCCUCACCUUAUCUGACCCUGGCUCCUGGGCCACCCACUUGCCACUUGGAAUAUUUAUUGUCUAACUGAUUUUCCAGUAUUAAGGAUUUUACAGGUUUACACUGGAAUUAGAAGUUCAUCUGAACUGCCUGUGAUGUCCCUGCUGGUUUCCCAAUGGCCAGGCACUGCAGAGAUGUAUAAGAUACGAGAAUACAGUCACCUAAAGACAUGGGAAGUUUUGUAAGCAAUGUCUCCCGAGAUUCCCCAUUCUAAAUAUGGCAAGGAGUGUUUUAAGUACUUCAUGCUUGAAGCUUUUCAUGCAUUUCCAUCGUUGCAGUUGGACCAGUUUUAAAAUAUAUAUAUCAUAAAUAAUCUUCAGAACAUUUUAAUGUACUACCGAUGGUAUUAAAAGUCAAAGCUUUCACAAAAUUUAAUUUACUUCUCCCUGUAACUUAAGAACAGUUUUAAAAUGUGCAUGGCUCCUGCUAAAUUUAACAGCUUCCCCUUUUGCCUUCUCGACUGGAGGCUGCAACAACCUGAGCCAGGAGGUCUGGCGACUACAAUGUUUGAGUGAAGCUGUGAGAUCCAUGCCUGUACUGGAAGCUCCUGACAGCCUCUGCAGGGCCUUGGUGCCAGGCUCCGGGGGUGGUGGGGGAGUGGGCUUUCCUUCUUAGAAAGCCUCUAGGCUUUGCAGGUUCAGGAAGAAGCUCACCAGCUGGGUCCAGCCACUGAAAGGAACCCUGAGCCUCAGUUUGCAGCCCAGAGAUGCUCCGGGGUCUCGCCCAGUGCAUAUUCCUGGAGAGCUACAACAUCAGGGCAUCAGAUCCACAGAAGAUACAUGUGCUUCACUAUACACCAGGAGAUGUUGGCACACCUGAAACCAUGGCCCCAACCAUUGUGGUUCCCCCGGGCAACAGAAGUGUGGUGGCUGGAUCCAGUGAGACCACCUUGGAAUGUAUAGCCAGUGCCAGGCCUGUGGAGGACCUGAGUGUGACCUGGAAGAGGAAUGGAGUGAGAAUCACCAGUGGCCUCCACAGCUUUGGAAGACGCCUCACCAUCAGCAACCCGACGUCCGCGGACACCGGGCCAUACGUCUGCGAGGCGGCGCUGCCGGGGAGCGCUUUUGAACCGGCCAGGGCGACGGCCUUUCUUUUCAUCAUAGAGCCACCAUAUUUUACUGCUGAGCCCGAGAGUCGGAUUUCAGCUGAAGUAGAAGAAACUGUGGACAUCGGAUGUCAAGCCAUGGGGGUCCCCCUUCCCACCCUCCAGUGGUACAAGGAUGCCAUCUCCAUCAGCAGGCUCCAGAAUCCUCGAUACAAAGUGCUCGCCAGCGGAGGCCUGCGCAUCCAGAAGCUGCGUCCAGAGGACUCCGGAAUCUUCCAGUGCUUCGCCAGCAAUGAAGGAGGGGAGAUCCAGACCCACACCUACCUGGAUGUAACCAAUAUCGCUCCAGUGUUCACCCAGCGGCCAGUGGACACCACAGUUACUGACGGGAUGACAGCCAUUCUAAGGUGUGAGGUGUCCGGGGCUCCCAAACCCGCCAUCACCUGGAAAAGAGAAAACCACAUUCUGGCCAGUGGCUCUGUCCGGAUUCCUAGGUUCAUGCUUCUUGAAUCGGGGGGUCUACAGAUCGCGCCCGUCUUCAUCCAGGAUGCCGGCAACUACACCUGCUAUGCGGCCAACACAGAGGGCUCCCUGAAUGCAUCGGCCACGCUCACUGUGUGGAAUCGGACGUCCAUCGUCCACCCUCCUGAGGACCACGUGGUGAUUAAGGGGACCACGGCCACGCUGCACUGUGGUGCCACACAUGACCCCCGGGUUUCACUCCGCUACGUUUGGAAGAAGGACAACGUGGCCCUGACUCCAUCGAGCACGUCUAGGAUCGUGGUGGAGAAGGACGGGUCCCUUCUCAUCAGCCAGACGUGGUCAGGCGACAUCGGUGACUACAGCUGCGAGAUUGUUUCUGAAGGAGGGAAUGACUCCAGGAUGGCCCGGCUGGAAGUGAUUGAACUGCCUCAUUCACCUCAGAACCUCCUGGUCAGCCCUAAUUCUUCCCACAGCCACGCCGUGGUGCUCUCUUGGGUCCGGCCCUUUGAUGGAAACAGUCCUAUUCUUUAUUACAUCGUGGAGCUCUCUGAAAACAACUCUCCAUGGAAGGUGCAUCUGUCAAACGUUGGCCCUGAGAUGACAGGCGUCACCGUGAGUGGCCUGACUCCGGCUCGUACCUAUCAAUUCCGGGUGUGCGCGGUGAAUGAAGUGGGCAGGGGCCAGUACAGCGCCGAGACAAGCAGGUUGAUGCUACCUGAAGAACCACCCAGUGCUCCCCCGAAAAAUAUAGUGGCCAGUGGGCGGACUAAUCAGUCCAUUAUGGUCCAGUGGCAGCCACCCCCAGAAACAGAGCACAACGGGGUGUUGCGUGGAUACAUCCUCAGGUACCGCCUGGCUGGCCUUCCCGGAGAGUACCAGCAGCGGAACAUCACCAGCCCGGAGGUGAACUACUGCCUGGUGACAGACCUGAUCAUCUGGACACAGUAUGAGAUACAGGUGGCGGCGUACAACGGGGCCGGUCUGGGCGUCUUCAGCAGGGCAGUGACCGAGUACACCUUGCAGGGAGUGCCCACCGCGCCCCCGCAGAACGUGCAGACGGAAGCCGUGAACUCCACCACCAUUCAGUUCCUGUGGAACCCUCCGCCUCAGCAGUUUAUCAAUGGCAUCAACCAGGGAUACAAGCUUCUGGCAUGGCCGGCAGAUGCCCCCGAGGCUGUCACUGUGGUCACUAUUGCCCCAGAUUUCCACGGAGUCCACCAUGGACACAUAACGAACCUGAAGAAGUUUACCGCCUACUUCACUUCCGUUCUGUGCUUCACCACCCCUGGGGACGGGCCUCCCAGCACACCUCAGCUGGUCUGGACUCAGGAAGACAAACCAGGAGCUGUGGGACAUCUGAGUUUCACAGAGAUCUUGGACACAUCUCUCAAGGUCAGCUGGCAGGAGCCCCUGGAGAAAAAUGGCAUCAUUACUGGCUAUCAGAUCUCUUGGGAAGUGUACGGCAGGAACGACUCUCGUCUCACGCACACCCUGAACAGCACGACGCACGAGUACAAGAUCCAAGGCCUCUCAUCUCUCACCACCUACACCAUCGACGUGGCCGCUGUGACUGCCGUGGGCACUGGCCUGGUGACUUCAUCCACCAUUUCUUCUGGAGUGCCCCCAGACCUUCCUGGUGCCCCAUCCAACCUGGUCAUUUCCAACAUCAGCCCUCGCUCCGCCACCCUUCAGUUCCGGCCAGGCUAUGACGGGAAAACGUCCAUCUCCAGGUGGAUUGUUGAGGGGCAGGUGGGAGCUAUCGGCGACGAGGAGGAGUGGGUCACCCUCUAUGAAGAGGAGAAUGAGCCUGAUGCCCAGAUGCUGGAGAUCCCAAACCUCACACCCUACACUCACUACAGAUUUCGAAUGAAGCAAGUGAACAUUGUUGGGCCGAGCCCCUACAGUCCGUCUUCCCGGGUCAUCCAGACCCUGCAGGCCCCACCCGACGUGGCUCCAACCAGCGUCACGGUCCGUACUGCCAGUGAGACCAGCCUGCGGCUUCGCUGGGUGCCCCUGCCGGAUUCUCAGUACAACGGGAACCCCGAGUCCGUGGGCUACAGGAUUAAGUACUGGCGCUCAGACCUCCAGUCCUCAGCAGUGGCCCAAGUCGUCAGUGACCGGCUGGAGAGAGAAUUCACCAUCGAGGAGCUGGAGGAGUGGAUGGAAUACGAGCUGCAGAUGCAGGCCUUCAACGCCGUCGGGGCUGGGCCGUGGAGCGAGGUGGUGCGGGGCCGGACGCGGGAGUCAGUUCCUUCAGCCGCCCCUGAGAACGUGUCAGCCGAGGCUGUCAGCUCGACCCAGAUUUUACUGACAUGGACAUCCGUGCCGGAACAGGACCAGAAUGGGCUCAUACUGGGCUACAAGAUCCUGUUCCGGGCCAAAGACCUGGAUCCCGAGCCCAGGAGCCACAUCGUGCGAGGGAACCACACGCAGUCGGCCCUGCUGGCAGGCCUGCGCAAGUUCGUGCUCUACGAGCUCCAGGUGCUGGCGUUCACCCGCAUCGGGAACGGGGUCCCCAGCACGCCCCUCAUCCUGGAGCGCACCAAAGACGAUGCCCCAGGCCCACCAGUGAGGCUCGUGUUCCCCGAAGUGAGACUCACCUCCGUGCGGAUAGUGUGGCAACCUCCGGAGGAGCCCAACGGCAUCAUCCUGGGGUACCAGAUUGCCUACCGCCUGGCCAGCAGCAGCCCCCACACCUUCACCACCGUGGAGGUCGGCGCCACAGUGAGGCAGUUCACAGCCACCGACCUGGCCCCGGAGUCCGCAUACAUCUUCAGGCUGUCCGCCAAGACGAGGCAGGGCUGGGGGGAGCCACUGGAGGCCACCGUCAUCACCACCGAGAAGAGAGAGCGGCCGGCACCCCCCAGAGAGCUCCUGGUGCCCCAGGCAGAAGUGACCGCACGCAGCCUCCGGCUCCAGUGGGUCCCGGGCAGCGACGGGGCCUCCCCCAUCCGGUACUUCACCAUGCAGGUGCGAGAGCUGCCUCGGGGUGAGUGGCAGACCUACUCCUCGUCCAUCAGCCAUGAGGCGACAGCAUGCGUCGUUGACAGACUGAGGCCCUUCACCUCCUACAAGCUGCGCCUGAAAGCCACCAACGACAUUGGGGACAGUGACUUCAGUUCAGAGACAGAGGCGGUGACCACGCUGCAGGAUGUUCCAGGAGAGCCCCCGGGAUCUGUCUCAGCGACGCCACACACCACGUCCUCUGUCCUGAUACAGUGGCAGCCUCCGAGGGACGAAAGCCUGAAUGGCCUUCUUCAGGGAUACAGGAUCUACUACAGGGAGCUGGAGUAUGAAGCCGGGUCAGGCACUGAGGCCAAGACGCUCAAAAACCCUAUAGCUUUACAUGCUGAGCUCACAGCCCAAAGCAGCUUCAAGACGGUGAACAGCAGCUCCACAUCGACGAUGUGUGAACUAACACAUUUAAAGAAGUACCGGCGCUAUGAAGUAAUAAUGACCGCCUAUAACAUCAUCGGCGAGAGCCCAGCCAGCGCGCCCGUGGAGGUCUUUGUCGGCGAGGCUGCCCCGGCCAUGGCCCCGCAGAACGUGCAGGUGACCCCACUCACGGCCAGCCAGCUGGAGGUCACGUGGGACCCACCACCCCCGGAGAGCCAGAAUGGGAACAUCCAAGGCUACAAGAUUUACUACUGGGAGGCAGACAGCCAGAACGAAACGGAGAAAAUGAAGGUCCUCUUCCUCCCCGAGCCCGUGGUGAGGCUGAAGAACCUGACCAGCCAUACCAAGUACCUGGUCAGCAUAUCAGCCUUCAACGCCGCCGGAGAUGGACCUAAGAGUGACCCCCAGCAGGGGCGCACCCACCAGGCCGCCCCUGGGGCCCCCAGCUUUCUGGCGUUCUCAGAAAUAACCUCCACCACGCUCAACGUGUCCUGGGGCGAGCCUGCGGCGGCCAACGGCAUCCUGCAGGGCUAUCGGGUGGUGUACGAGCCCUUGGCCCCUGUACAAGGGGUGAGCAAGGUGGUGACCGUGGAAGUGAGAGGGAACUGGCAGCGCUGGCUGAAGGUGCGGGACCUCACCAAGGGAGUGACCUAUUUCUUCCGUGUCCAAGCGCGGACCAUCACCUACGGGCCCGAGCUCCAAGCCAAUAUCACAGCCGGGCCAGCCGAGGGAUCCCCGGGCUCGCCUAGAGAUGUCCUGGUCACCAAGUCCGCCUCUGAACUGACGCUGCAGUGGACUGAGGGACACUCUGGCGACACACCUACCACGGGCUAUGUGAUCGAGGCCCGGCCCUCAGAUGAAGGCUUAUGGGACAUGUUUGUGAAGGACAUCCCGCGGAGCGCCACAUCCUACACCCUCAGCCUGGAUAAGCUCCGGCAAGGAGUGACUUACGAGUUCCGGGUGGUGGCUGUGAAUGAGGCGGGCUACGGGGAGCCCAGCAACCCCUCCACGGCUGUGUCAGCUCAAGUGGAAGCCCCAUUCUACGAGGAGUGGUGGUUCCUCCUGGUGAUGGCUCUGUCCAGCCUGAUCGUCAUCCUGCUGGUGGUGUUCGCCCUCGUCCUGCACGGGCAGAAUAAGAAGUAUAAGAACUGCAGCACAGGAAAGGGGAUCUCCACCAUGGAGGAGUCUGUGACCCUGGACAACGGAGGAUUUGCUGCCCUGGAGCUCAGCAGCCGCCACCUCAAUGUCAAGAGCACCUUCUCCAAGAAGAACGGGACCAGGUCCCCACCCCGGCCUAGCCCCGGCGGCCUGCACUACUCAGACGAGGACAUCUGCAACAAGUACAACGGCGCCGUGCUGACCGAGAGCGUGAGCCUCAAGGAGAAGUCGGCAGAUGCAUCAGAAUCUGAGGCCACGGACUCUGACUACGAGGACGCGCUGCCCAAGCACUCCUUCGUGAACCACUACAUGAGCGACCCCACCUACUACAACUCAUGGAAGCGCAGGGCCCAGGGCCGCGCACCUGCGCCGCACAGGUACGAGGCGGUGGCGGGCUCCGAGGCGGGCGCGCAGCUGCACCCGGUCAUCACCACGCAGAGCGCGGGCGGCGUCUACACCCCCGCUGGCCCCGGCGCGCGAACUCCGCUCACCGGCUUCUCCUCCUUCGUGUGAGCAAAGCGCCGCGCCUCCCUCAGGGCGGAACGGAGGCAACUUUCCGGAGUCUAUUUUUGUUAAGACAAUCAACUCCAAUAACUGAGCUGAAGUUUUUGUUUAAAAAGAAAAAAAUCUGAUAAGUGAUGAUUUUACCUACUUGUGGACACUAGAUUUCAAUUAGGAAGGUUUUUUUAAACGGCUUUUUGUAACUUCGCUGCAGGAAGCAGGUUUGUUUCUUUUUCUUUUCUUUUUAAGAGAAGGUGUAUUUCACUGGUGCAAUGGCUUGGCACCUCCGGGGCCUGGGAGGACCUCAGACCUCCCCAGCCCUGGGUUUCUCCGUCUUCAAGACCAACUAGGAAGGGUCAAGCGGGGAGAGGGAGUGGAGGGUCAGGUGAGAUCUCAGAGCUGCCCCGGCCGGCCCCCGUCUCUUUCUACCUCCUCUUCCAGAGAACCAGCGGCUCACACCCUUCUCAACGCAGGACAUCCUCGGCGGCUCCUGGGGUUUGAAGAGCAAACGUUUUUCCCUGGGCUCAGUGCGUUUUGUCCCAACUUCAUCUGUUUCUGAAAUGUUCUCACUUGGCAGUGUCUAGUCAAGGAGUCGGCUUUCAGGUUCCUGACGGCCAGGCAGGGAUGCUAAGGUGUGGCUCAGCCGUCACUGUCUGUGUCACUGCAGUGGUGCGGUCCUCAGGCUUUUCUGCCUGUCUUUCCCCCUUCCUUCUCACCUGACAGCGAGGGAGAGGGAAGCCUCUUAGGGCUGGAAGCCACCACGCUGGCCCUCUCCUUCCCCGAACACAGCACACGGUCAACUCCGCGGGACACGAGGACACGGGACGGCGUCUCCAGAAUUGCUUGUUACGUAGGAAGCGUGCAUUGUUAACCAGAGUAUUUUUAAAAUCUUUUUAUCUUUUUUUAAACUAUGUCACAUGAAAUGAAUGCGUCUUUGCUGUCUCCAGGUGCCUUUUUAUUAAUUGUUCAGCUUUGUACAUGGGAAAGAUGAAAAGCAACAGUGUCUGCAAAUAAAGCAAAACAGCUCUGAGAACACACGCUCCCGACUCGCCUCGUGCACACCAGGCCGUCCCCUCCCUCUGUCCUGGCUUCUGCUGGCUGCUCGCAGCAGCCACCGCUUCUCCACCACUGGCGCUGCUGCUGCCCCCUCUCCCAGUCCGAGGCCAGCUUUUAGCCUUAACAGGUUUUUUGGAAAUGUUUCUUUUUUUUAUUUAAAAUUGUCAUUGUUUGGUUUAAAUUUUUCAGCUAGAUGAAAAGAGUAUGAACUACUUUGGAAAACUUAACAGCUCAGAGAUGGCCAUGCCUCCAGCCCCUCACGUCAUCUUUGCAACAGACGACUGGGCUGCCAUGGUCCACCCCUCAGCCCGGGUCCCGGGUCUGGAUGGAACGGGAGCACUGCUGGUGCCCACUGGCGUGUGUGCCCCGGGUCCCUGUAAGUGCCCCCUCACCAGCAGCAGCGUGACACACACAAGACUCAAGACCACCCUGUCAGUGCCCCCCAGUGCACGGCAAACGGGCAGGUGCCGUUCCCCCAGUGACCUGAGGGUAGGGGACAACUGAGCAGUAUCUGACCAGUGCCACCCAGGAGCCAGUCUCCUGGCCACAUGCAGAAAGUGUGGCCCCUGCUUACCUAGAUGUUUUGUGCACCUCCAUGGGCAGAGGGUGUGGAUAUUGCCUGGAUUCUGUGCUGUCAGCGUUGCUGAGUAUGGCCCCAGGAGACCAAGGAGAGUUUUGUAUAGGCUGGAAAACCCCUUUUCAGUCUUUCCAAAAUUAGAGGGUAUGGCAAGUUUCCUUUUUUCUCUCCUCCCUUCCUUCCCCUCCUUCCUUUCCUUUACCCCUCCUUUCCUUCCUUCCUCCCUUCCUCUCUUCUUUCCUCCCUCCCUCCCUCCUUCCCUCCCUUCCUUCCUCUCUUUCCUCCUUCCUUCCCUCCCUUCUUUCCCUCCCUCCCUUCCUCUCUCCCCUAUUCCUUCUUCCUUUUCUCCUCCUUUUUCUGAGUGGAGGGGGAAAUAUUCUAAACCAAAAAUCCUAGAUGCUCUGCCCAAAGCCACUUCUGCAUGAGAAUCGCAACCCACAGUUCCCCGGAUGAGACUCACCACAGUGGACAGUGCCACCUCCUUCCCCUCGGCCCCGGAGAGGGCGAAGUGGGCGGGAAGCCAGGAUGUGAGCACUGGAAUUUCUUGGAAGAGAAGCGAUAAAUGGAGACCAUGGCCAGCGCUGCUUUCUGUGCACUCUGAUGACUGCUCUCUGCAGCCAUGAGGAUGUGGCUUUACAUGCCAGGGAGAGUGUUGAGACGUCUUAGGUUGAGGAUGAGCAGAUUCGAGAUAUGUUUGUUGCUCUCGGGUUUUCGAUACAACAUCAUGACACUUCUGUUUCAAGCUCAUGUUUUCCGUCUCCCCUCCACUCUUAGUAAACCUUGAUCUGUACGGAGCGGCCUGUCCGAGGCUACGCCGGCCUCCUGGCUGCUGCUGGACUGUGCUUAGGACAGCGCCCAUGCCUCGGAGGGACUCUGUCCCAUGAGAACCACCUGUGCAAAGGAACAGAGCUGGAUGUUUCCAGGUAGAUUUUGGCCUCCCAGAGCAAUGCGGCAUUUGAGAAGCAACAGUUCCUAACUCCUUAUCUUCAGGGAAGGAAAAGAAAAUCACAGCCUAGGAAGAUGGAGGUUGGAUUUUAAUCUCGGUUUUAAAAAGAGGACAAACAAAAUGUCUCUAAGCCAGGCUAGAUGGAAUGUGCUCCCGCUCUCUCCUGCCGUGCUGAAAGUCAUGCCUUGCGGAUGCCUCAUGACAGCAGUGGCUGAGUCUCCCCACCCACCCCCAACGUGGCUCAUUUCAGAUUGCUUCGGCCCCACCCUGCAAGGAUGUGGUCACGGAGUGGCCAGGAGGCUCCGUCUGAGCCACAGGGAUGGGUGUGCAGAGCUCCCUCCUCCUGGGGUGCCAGGGCAGAGAUUCCAGGCAGGUGAGCCCAGAGAGAGCUGCCAGGCCACACCCCCUCGGCCUCCUGCACGGCCACCUUCUGGGUGAAUCGGUCCAGCCCAAGCCCCUCUCCCCAGCCUCGCCUUCAGCCUCUCUCCCAGCCUGCUUUUAUAAGGCGCACUUCACUCAAUGCUGUAGCCAAAAAACGAGGGGCCCCAGGGAGAGGGGACCCAGAUGGCCACACACGGAACGCGCCUCCACAGCCCCGGGAGGUGGCUCACUCUGUACAGGUCUUCGGAGGCCGUGUUUGUAUCUAACUGUGACUGGGCUGAAGCAUGAUGUUUGCCUAAUGGUUCGUAGCAUGGUUUUUAUUUCUUACGCAUUCUUGGCACACAGUGUAGCUAUCCUCCUGACGAGCAACCCGUCUGCGUACCUAAGUGUGGCUCCCCGUGGGUCAGCGUCCUGGUAGCAUGGAUCCAGUCUGAAAGGUGAGGACAACGUGGAAACUCAUGAGCUGAGCCUGCCCGCUGGGACACGUCUCCUUCCCGCGUCACCUUCUGGUUUAGGGAGCCGUCAGGUCCCUAAACGUUCCCUACAACUUUUUCUGAAAUUGUGCAGAAAAACAGAUCUCAUUAAAAGAAAAAAAGAAACAACUUGUAGGAAGACAGAGAGGUGCUAUGGGUACAAUUUUUAAUAAAAACAUUAUUUUGUUCCUUAAA